AGAGCCAGAGCGGCGGGAGCCGGUCCUGGGCGCGUUGCCCCGGGAGCGCCCGUCGUCCGGGCAGAGCGCAGCCGCAACCGCGACCACAGCCGCAGUCGCUUUCCAGCCUGCCUUCGGUGCGCAGCGGGGGAACAGGGCUAGUGCAGCCGCCGGAGGGGGGCACGGGCUCCUCUCCCAUCCCAGAGCUACUGGGCUGCCCUUGCUGUCCUCGCCGCCCCAGCAGACCCCGGCCGGACCUGCCACCUGCGCCCUGGUUGCGCCAUGGAUCCUUCGGAAAAGAAGAUAUCGGUGUGGAUCUGCCAGGAAGAGAAGCUGGUGUCCGGCCUCUCCCGCCGCACCACUUGCUCCGACGUUGUGCGAGUGCUUUUGGAGGACGGCUGCCGGCGGCGACGGAGACAGCGGCGGAGCCGGCGGCUGGGGUCGGCCGGCGACCCGCAUGGCCCGGGAGAGCUGCCCGAACCCCCGAACGAGGACGACGAGGACGACGACGAGGCGCUGCCGCAGGGCAUGCUGUGCGGGCCCCCGCAGUGCUAUUGCAUCGUGGAGAAGUGGCGCGGCUUUGAGCGCAUCCUCCCCAACAAGACGCGCAUCUUGCGCCUCUGGGCUGCCUGGGGCGAAGAGCAAGAGAAUGUGCGCUUCGUGCUAGUGCGCAGCGAGGCAUCGCUGCCUAACGCCGGCCCCCGCAGCGCCGAGGCGCGCGUAGUGCUGAGCCGAGAGCGCCCCUGUCCGGCCCGCGGGGCCCCGGCGCGGCCCAGCCUGGCCAUGACCCAGGAGAAACAGCGGCGAGUGGUGCGCAAGGCCUUUCGCAAACUGGCCAAGCUCAACCGGCGGCGCCAGCAGCAGACACCGUCGUCCUGUUCGUCCACUUCGUCGUCCACUGCCUCGUCCUGCUCUUCGUCGCCGCGGACCCACGAGAGCGCGUCGGUGGAGCGCAUGGAGACGCUGGUGCAUCUGGUGCUUUCCCAGGACCACACAAUUCGCCAGCAGGUGCAGCGGCUCCACGAGCUGGACCGCGAGAUCGAUCACUACGAGGCCAAGGUGCACCUGGACCGCAUGCGGCGUCACGGGGUCAACUACGUGCAGGACACUUACUUGGUUGGGGCAGGCAUCGAGCUCGACGGGUCCAGACCGGGAGAGGAGCCAGAAGAGGUGGCGGCGGAGGCGGAGGAGGCGGCGGCGGCGCCCCCUCUAGCCGGCGAGGCGCAGGCGGCGGCGCUGGAGGAGCUGGCCCGGCGCUGCGACGACUUGCUGCGGCUUCAGGAGCAACGGGUUCAGCAGGAGGAGUUGCUGGAGCGCCUUUCAGCCGAGAUUCAGGAGGAACUCAACCAGAGGUGGAUGCGACGGCGCCAGGAGGAGCUGGCGGCGCGGGAGGAGCCCCUGGAGCCCGACGGUGGCCCCGACGGCGAGCUGCUGCUGGAGCAGGAACGGGUCAGGACGCAGCUCAGUACCAGCCUUUACAUUGGGCUGCGGCUCAACACGGACCUAGAGGCCGUCAAGUCGGACUUGGAUUACAGCCAGCAGCAAUGGGACAGCAAGAAGCGCGAGCUACAGGGCCUUCUGCAAACUUUGCACACUUUGGAGCUGACGGUGGCACCGGAUGGGGCUCCUGGCUCUGGCAGUCCCUCGCGGGAACCUGGGCCUCAAGCCUGCGCCGACAUGUGGGUGGACCAGGCCCGUGGACUGGCCAAGAGCGGUCCUGGCAACGACGAAGACUCGGAUACGGGACUGAGCUCUAUGCAUAGCCAAGACUCGGACUCCUUGCCCAUGUGCGAAUCCCUUGUGUAGGGGUGGGGGGCGGGGGGCGGGGGGCGGGAACAGGGGGAUUCUUUUUUCUUGCAGAAUGCAGUGGGCCAGCCGGCUCGCGGACUUGAAACCAGGCUGUUGCGAGCCCAGAGCUCCGGCUGGGCAGCAGCGCUCUGCGCAGCCUCGCGCUCAUCUGGCUCCGGGGUGAGUGCAGAGCAGGGUGAGGGUAGAAGAAGUAGGAUCCUCAAUACAAGCUCAUUAAAGAGAGGGAAGGAGGGAGGAGGCAAGAACCCCCUAUACUGGAAAACAAACAACCCAAGGAAAUUGACGUGGUCCGAGCCCAUUUUCAAAGUAAGGAAGUAUAAUGGAGAUUUCGCUACUCUUCUGUAUGGGAAGGACUGAUGGCAGCUAGAACUUUAGUUUGUGGUAUGAAGUGCUUUAAAAGAAACACUUGGAUGAAAAGGAAAUUCCUUGAAUGUUAAUUGUGACUGUAAACGUGUUAAAACUAGCCAAAGAGGACGCACUGGUGUCGGUCUCUGCCUUUCUUACCUCUUUGAUAAAACCCAUAGGCACCAAAAUCCUGGCUGUUUACAUUUCUGCAGAUUUGGGAAUUACCCAUCUGCUAAAUCAUUUGUCUUUUAUUUUCUUUCAAAGGCUAAACUGUAUCGAAGUCUAACCCUGUAUUUCCUCCUAGUAAACACAAUAGAUGUUAAAAGGGAAUUCUUUUCCCAAAAUAACCUUUUAUUAUUACAAAAGCCAAACAUAAUCAUUUGAGAUAUAAAAUCCUGGCAAACAUAAUCGUGGUUAAAAUUUAAUCUGGGCCCUUUGGGAUCUGUCCCUUCAAAGGCAGGUGAGUUGCCCUUUAAUUCGUAUUGCCACUUCAUUGACUCAAUCACUGUUAUUUCAGAAAAAAAUAAAAGGAAGUAGCAGAAUUCAAGUUACGCAAAACAAAACUUGCUGUCUAACAAGCACUCUUUGAAAGCAAAGAUGUUUUAGUGUUCAGCUUUUAAAUUGAGCUAUGUGAUUAAAACCAACCAUGACCUUAACGGAUUUUACCCAAA